GGGCGGGCCGGCUGGCUGGGAAGAUGGCGGCGGGAACCUGGGCCGCCGCCGCCGCCGCCGCCGCCGCCGCGGAGCGAACCAGGGGUGUCCGGGGUGCGCGGUCCAGGGCCGGGGCCGGGCCAUGAGCGCGCCGUCCUCGAGUCCCCGAGCCGCGGAGCCCGCCCGCGCCCCUCGGGCCGCCCCGCGUCCCUCGCCAUGGCGCGGCUCGCGGACUACUUCGUGCUGGUGGCGUUCGGGCCGCACCCGCGCGGGAGUGGGGAAGGCCAGGGCCAGAUUCUGCAGCGCUUCCCAGAGAAGGACUGGGAGGACAACCCAUUCCCCCAGGGCAUCGAGCUGUUUUGCCAGCCCAGCGGGUGGCAGCUGUGUCCCGAGAGGAAUCCACCGACCUUCUUUGUUGCUGUCCUCACCGACAUCAACUCCGAGCGCCACUACUGCGCCUGCUUGACCUUCUGGGAGCCAGCGGAGCCUUCACAGCAGGAAACGACGCGCGUGGAGGAUGCCACAGAGAGGGAGGAAGAGGGGGAUGAGGGAGGCCAGACCCACCUGUCUCCCACAGCACCUGCCCCAUCUGCCCAGCUGUUUGCACCGAAGACGCUGGUACUGGUGUCGCGACUCGACCACACGGAGGUGUUCAGGAACAGCCUUGGCCUCAUCUAUGCCAUCCACGUGGAGGGCCUGAAUGUGUGCCUGGAGAACGUGAUUGGGAACCUGCUGACGUGCACUGUGCCCCUGGCUGGGGGCUCGCAGAGGACGAUCUCUUUGGGGGCUGGUGACCGGCAGGUCAUCCAGACUCCACUGGCCGACUCGCUGCCCGUCAGCCGCUGCAGCGUGGCCCUGCUCUUCCGCCAGCUAGGCAUCACCAACGUGCUGUCUUUGUUCUGUGCCGCCCUCACGGAGCACAAGGUUCUCUUCCUGUCCCGGAGCUACCAGCGGCUCGCCGAUGCCUGUAGGGGCCUCCUGGCACUGCUGUUUCCUCUCAGAUACAGCUUCACCUAUGUGCCCAUCCUGCCGGCUCAGCUGCUGGAGGUCCUCAGCACACCCACGCCCUUCAUCAUUGGGGUCAACGCGGCCUUCCAGGCAGAGACCCAGGAGCUGCUCGAUGUGAUUGUUGCUGAUCUGGAUGGAGGGACGGUCACCAUUCCUGAGUGUGUGCACAUUCCACCCUUGCCAGAGCCACUGCAGAGUCAGACGCACAGUGUGCUGAGCAUGGUCCUGGACCCGGAGCUGGAGUUGGCUGACCUCGCCUUCCCUCCGCCCACGACAUCCACCUCCUCCCUGAAGAUGCAGGACAAGGAGCUGCGCGCGGUCUUCCUGCGGCUGUUCGCUCAGCUGCUGCAGGGCUAUCGCUGGUGCCUGCACGUCGUGCGCAUCCACCCGGAGCCUGUCAUCCGCUUCCAUAAGGCAGCCUUCCUGGGCCAGCGUGGGCUGGUAGAGGACGAUUUCCUGAUGAAGGUGCUGGAGGGCAUGGCCUUUGCUGGCUUUGUGUCAGAGCGUGGGGUCCCAUACCGCCCUACGGACCUGUUCGAUGAGCUGGUGGCCCACGAGGUGGCAAGGAUGCGGGCGGAUGAGAACCACCCCCAGCGUGUCCUGCGUCACGUCCAGGAACUGGCAGAGCAGCUCUACAAGAACGAGAACCCGUACCCAGCCGUGGCGAUGCACAAGGUACAGAGGCCCGGUGAGAGCAGCCACCUGCGACGGGUGCCCCGACCCUUCCCCCGGCUGGAUGAGGGCACCGUGCAGUGGAUCGUGGACCAGGCUGCAGCCAAGAUGCAGGGUGCACCCCCAGCUGUGAAGGCCGAGAGGAGGACCACCGUGCCCUCAGGGCCCCCCAUGACUGCCAUACUGGAGCGGUGCAGUGGGCUGCAUGUCAACAGCGCCCGGCGGCUGGAGGUUGUGCGCAACUGCAUCUCCUACGUGUUUGAGGGGAAAAUGCUUGAGGCCAAGAAGCUGCUCCCAGCCGUGUUGAGGGCCCUGAAGGGGCGAGCUGCCCGCCGCUGCCUCGCCCAGGAGCUGCACCUGCAUGUGCAGCAGAACCGUGCGGUCCUGGACCACCAGCAGUUUGACUUUGUCGUCCGUAUGAUGAACUGCUGCCUGCAGGACUGCACUUCUCUGGACGAGCAUGGCAUUGCGGCGGCUCUGCUGCCUCUGGUCACAGCCUUCUGCCGGAAGCUGAGCCCGGGGGUGACGCAGUUUGCAUACAGCUGUGUGCAGGAGCACGUGGUGUGGAGCACGCCACAGUUCUGGGAGGCCAUGUUCUAUGGGGAUGUGCAGACUCACAUCCGGGCCCUCUACCUGGAGCCCACGGAGGACCUGGCCCCCGCCCAGGAGGUUGGGGAGGCACCUUCCCAGGAGGACGAGCGCUCUGCCCUAGACGUGGCUUCUGAGCAGCGGCGCUUGUGGCCAACUCUGAGUCGUGAGAAGCAGCAGGAGCUGGUGCAGAAGGAGGAGAGCACGGUGUUCAGCCAGGCCAUCCACUAUGCCAACCGCAUGAGCUACCUCCUCCUGCCCCUGGACAGCAGCAAGAGCCGCCUACUUCGGGAGCGUGCCGGGCUGGGCGACCUGGAGAGCGCCAGCAACAGCCUGGUCACCAACAGCAUGGCUGGCAGUGUGGCCGAGAGCUAUGACACGGAGAGCGGCUUCGAGGAUGCAGAGACCUGCGACGUAGCUGGGGCUGUGGUCCGCUUCAUCAACCGCUUUGUGGACAAGGUCUGCACGGAGAGUGGGGUCACCAGCGACCACCUCAAGGGGCUGCAUGUCAUGGUGCCAGACAUUGUCCAGAUGCACAUCGAGACCCUGGAGGCCGUGCAGCGGGAGAGCCGGAGGCUGCCGCCCAUCCAGAAGCCCAAGCUGCUGCGGCCGCGCCUGCUGCCGGGUGAGGAGUGUGUGCUGGACGGCCUGCGCGUCUACCUGCUGCCGGAUGGGCGUGAGGAGGGCGCGGGGGGCAGUGCUGGGGGACCAGCAUUGCUCCCAGCUGAGGGCGCCGUCUUCCUCACCACGUACCGGGUCAUCUUCACGGGGAUGCCCACGGACCCCCUGGUUGGGGAGCAGGUGGUGGUCCGCUCCUUCCCGGUGGCUGCGCUGACCAAGGAGAAGCGCAUCAGCGUCCAGACCCCUGUGGACCAGCUCCUGCAGGACGGGCUCCAGCUGCGCUCCUGCACAUUCCAGCUGCUGAAAAUGGCCUUUGACGAGGAGGUGGGGUCUGACAGCGCCGAGCUCUUCCGUAAGCAGCUGCAUAAGCUGCGGUACCCGCCGGACAUCAGGGCCACCUUUGCGUUCACCUUGGGCUCUGCCCACACACCUGGCCGGCCACCGCGAGUCACCAAGGACAAGGGUCCUUCCCUCAGAACCCUGUCCCGGAACCUGGUCAAGAACGCCAAGAAGACCAUCGGGCGGCAGCAUGUCACUCGCAAGAAGUACAACCCCCCCAGCUGGGAGCACCGGGGCCAGCCGCCCCCUGAGGACCAGGAGGACGAGAUCUCAGUGUCGGAGGAGCUGGAGCCCAGCACGCUGACCCCGUCCUCAGCCCUGAAGCCCUCCGACCGCAUGACCAUGAGCAGCCUGGUGGAAAGGGCUUGCUGUCGCGACUACCAGCGCCUCGGUCUGGGCACCCUGAGCAGCAGCCUGAGCCGGGCCAAGUCUGAGCCCUUCCGCAUUUCUCCGGUCAACCGCAUGUAUGCCAUCUGCCGCAGCUACCCAGGGCUGCUGAUCGUGCCCCAGAGUGUCCAGGACAACGCCCUGCAGCGCGUGUCCCGCUGCUACCGCCAGAACCGCUUCCCCGUGGUCUGCUGGCGCAGCGGGCGGUCCAAGGCGGUGCUGCUGCGCUCUGGAGGCCUGCAUGGCAAAGGUGUCGUCGGCCUCUUCAAGGCCCAGAACGCACCUUCUCCAGGCCAGUCCCAGGCGGACUCGAGUAGCCUGGAGCAGGAGAAGUACCUGCAGGCUGUGGUCAGCUCCAUGCCCCGCUACGCCGACGCGUCGGGACGCAACACGCUUAGCGGCUUCUCCUCAGCCCACAUGGGCAGUCACGUUCCCAGCCCCAGAGCCAGGGUCACCACGCUGUCCAACCCCAUGGCGGCCUCGGCCUCCAGACGGACCGCACCCCGAGGUAAGUGGGGCAGUGUCCGGACCAGUGGACGCAGCAGUGGCCUUGGCACCGAUGUGGGCUCCCGGCUAGCUGGCAGAGACGCGCUGGCCCCACCCCAGGCCAACGGGGGCCCUCCCGACCCGGGCUUCCUGCGUCCGCAGCGAGCAGCCCUCUAUAUCCUUGGGGACAAAGCCCAGCUCAAGGGUGUGCGGUCAGACCCCCUGCAGCAGUGGGAGCUGGUGCCCAUUGAGGUAUUCGAGGCACGGCAGGUGAAGGCUAGCUUCAAGAAGCUGCUGAAAGCAUGUGUCCCAGGCUGCCCCGCUGCUGAGCCCAGCCCAGCCUCCUUCCUGCGCUCACUGGAGGACUCAGAGUGGCUGAUCCAGAUCCACAAGCUGCUGCAGGUGUCUGUGCUGGUGGUGGAGCUCCUGGAUUCAGGCUCCUCCGUGCUGGUGGGCCUGGAGGAUGGCUGGGACAUCACCACCCAGGUGGUAUCCUUGGUGCAGCUGCUCUCAGACCCCUUCUACCGCACGCUGGAGGGCUUUCGCCUGCUGGUGGAGAAGGAGUGGCUGUCCUUCGGCCAUCGCUUCAGCCACCGUGGAGCUCACACCCUGGCCGGGCAGAGCAGCGGCUUCACACCCGUCUUCCUGCAGUUCCUGGACUGCGUACACCAGGUCCACCUGCAGUUCCCCAUGGAGUUUGAGUUCAGCCAGUUCUACCUCAAGUUCCUCGGCUACCACCAUGUGUCCCGCCGUUUCCGGACCUUCCUGCUCGACUCUGACUAUGAGCGCAUUGAGCUGGGGCUGCUGUAUGAGGAGAAGGGGGAACGCAGGGGCCAGGUGCCGUGCAGGUCUGUGUGGGAGUAUGUGGACCGGCUGAGCAAGAGGACGCCUGUGUUCCACAAUUACAUGUAUGCGCCCGAGGACGCAGAGGUCCUGCGGCCCUACAGCAACGUGUCCAACCUGAAGGUGUGGGACUUCUACACUGAGGAGACGCUGGCCGAGGGCCCUCCCUAUGACUGGGAACUGGCCCAGGGGCCCCCUGAACCCCCAGAGGAAGAACGGUCUGAUGGAGGCGCUCCCCAGAGCAGGCGCCGCGUGGUGUGGCCCUGUUACGACAGCUGCCCGCGGGCCCAGCCUGACGCCAUCUCACGCCUGCUGGAGGAGCUGCAGAGGCUGGAGACAGAGUUGGGCCAACCCGCUGAGCGCUGGAAGGACACCUGGGACCGGGUGAAGGCUGCACAGCGCCUCGAGGGCCGGCCAGACGGCCGUGGCACCCCUAGCUCCCUCCUUGUGUCCACCGCACCCCACCACCGUCGCUCGCUGGGUGUGUACCUGCAGGAGGGGCCCGUGGGCUCCACCCUGAGCCUCAGCCUGGACAGCGACCAGAGUAGUGGCUCAACCACAUCCGGCUCCCGUCAGGCUGCCCGCCGCAGCACCAGCACCCUGUACAGCCAGUUCCAGACAGCAGAGAGUGAGAACAGGUCCUACGAGGGCACUCUGUACAAGAAGGGGGCCUUCAUGAAGCCUUGGAAGGCCCGCUGGUUCGUGCUGGACAAGACCAAGCACCAGCUGCGCUACUACGACCACCGUGUGGACACAGAGUGCAAGGGUGUCAUCGACUUGGCGGAGGUGGAGGCUGUGGCACCUGGCACGCCCACUAUGGGUGCCCCUAAGACUGUGGACGAGAAGGCCUUCUUUGACGUGAAGACAACGCGUCGCGUUUACAACUUCUGUGCCCAGGACGUGCCCUCGGCCCAGCAGUGGGUGGACCGGAUCCAGAGCUGCCUGUCGGACGCCUGAGCCUCCCAGCCCUGCCCGGCUGCUCUGCUUCCGGUCGUUACCGACCACUAGGGGUGGGCAGGGCCGCCCCGGCCAUGUUUACAGCCCCGGCCCUCGACAGUAUUGAGGCCCCGAGCCCCCAGCACUUGUGUGUACAGCCCCCGUCCCCGCCCCGCCCCGCCCGGCCGGCCCUAACUUAUUUUGGCGUCACAGCUGAGCACCGUGCCGGGAGGUGGCCAAGGUACAGCCCGCAAUGGGCCUGUAAAUAGUCCGGCCCCGUCAGCGUGUGCUGGUCCAGCCAGCGGCUGCAGGCGAGUUUCUAGAACCAGAGUCUAUAUAAAGAGAGAACUAACGCCACGCUCCUGUGCCUGCCUUCCCCACUCCCCGGCUGCCUGCUCUCGGCCUACCCAGAGGGUCCCAUCUGCCCCUAUCCAGGCCCACCUGGCGGGAGGUUGGCAUCUUUCUCGUGAGCCUCUCCUGGUGCCUGGGUCCACCCAGCUCGGCCUGCAUGUCCCUGGGAGUGACUUUGCUCUGGGGGCGGAUCGAGCAGGAGGCUUCACUGGGGACUUGCUUGAUUCCCUCCACGCCUCAGGGCUGGUCUAGGGGCCGGCACGGCUGGAGAGGAAGCCCCCAUCCCUACCCAGGGGAUGCAGAAGCUGACCUCACAGAGGCUUGGGGGUGAAAGGGUGGGUGGUCAUUUGACCCCAGAAGGCUGUUGCAGGUCCAGAGGACACUUGAGGUGGACGUCAGUUUCUGGCUAGACCCGAGCUGAAGGGAUGGAGGCCGGAGGCGGGGGGGGGGGGGGGACAGUGGGCUCCCAGGGGAAUGCAGGUUGACCACAUCUGGCUCCUGCCAGGCAACGAGCAGCAUCUGGCAGAGUAAGGGGCCAACGCCCAUGGGGGAUGGACCCUCUCAGUUCUUGGGAAUUCUGCCCCAAAAGUCCUUUCCCUGGGGUCUCAGAGGGCCCCCGUCCUUCCCUUCUUGGUGUCACUGUGGCCCCUCACUGCUCUUUUCCUAUUCAAACCUGAGUCCCACCAGGCCCAGGGCUUCACCUGCUGAGCUGUUGUGUCCUUGCCUGUGACGAGGCCUGGCCAGGGGUGCAGGAGCAGAAGGUGGGGAGGGUUAUAGACGCUGCAAAGGCCAAGAGAACAUCUGAGAGUGGCAGCUGGUGACCUGGCCAGAGGGGCUGGUGAGGGGCAGAGAACCUGGCUAGAGGCUGGGUCCCUCAGGUGGUCCUCUCAGGUGGGAGGCGAGCAGCAGGUGUGGGUGAGGGGAAGGUUCUGAUGACAGCUGCAGAGGCAGGGCCCAGUGCUGGCAGGUGGGGGGCCAAGACCCUCCCCUGGUGGGACGUUGAAGCCAAGGAUGGCCUUGGACCCUGUCAGGCCCAGCAUGGUCCCGCCACCUCCCCCACCCCACAGGUGGUGUUGGGACACCUGGGCGAGAUGUGAGGGUGGGCUCACUUGAGCCACUGAAACCAGCCAGGUCUUCCCUCAGGCCGGACAGAUGGCGCCUGACCGAAGUUCCUGGCACCUGGAAAACCCACAGGUCAGAGUAAGGGGAGAAAGGACCCUGCCCUCCCUGUUCCACGUCUGUGGGGGGAGAGGACAAAUGCCAGGCACAGGGUAGGCGGCGAGAACAAGGCACUCAAUGUGUAGCUGGGGCAGAGACUCGGCCUCUGGGGAGCUGAGCGGGUUCCCUCCACCCCCAACCGUGGUGGAAAGACAAGCUCGCUGGGGCGGGGUGGGGGUCUGGUCUCCACCUGCCCCUCCCACUCAGCCACUGAGGACAAGGUGGGGCCCAGGCUUCUGGGAGGGGGAGCUGGCACAAAAGGAAGUCCUGGGGUUGAUGUGUUUGAGCGUUAGGCGAAGUGGUUCCCCCCAUCCCCCAAACGGAAAAAUGUCAGUAUUUGCUAAGCUGUAGAGACCUGAUGCCGUGAUGUGGCCUGUUCCGCCUCCACCCAUUACACGGGGAUAACGCUGGGGGGUGGCGGGCCCACAAAAGAGGUGCUGGAGGAGACUCUCCCACCCCUGGCCGGGCCGGGGCUUUGGGGCCGGAAGGUUCACAGUACGCGGUUUGUCCGAACGUCACGGCUUUUAUUGGGAGUUGGGGGUUUGGGGUGCCCUGUCAGGUGAUCAGAACAUUAAAAAUGGACUCAACGUAAAA